GUAUGGAUUGGCUGUAUCCUUACUCUCUCACUCCUCUGAAAGUGUCAGAAAGAUUUUUUAUUUUAUUAUUUUUUUUUUGAGAUGGAGUUUUGCUCUUGUUGCCCAGGCUGGAGUGCAAUGGUGUGAUCUUGGCUCACUGCAACCUCCACCUCCUGGGUUCAAGUGAUUAUCCUGCCUCAGCCUCGCAAGUAGCUGGGAUUACAGGUGUGAGCUACCAUGCCCAGCUAAUUUUUGUAUUUUUAGUAGAGACGGGGUUUCACCAUGUUGGCCAAGCUGGUCUUGAACUCAAGCUCAUGUUCCACCUGCCUUGGCCUCUCUACGUGCUGGGAUUACAGGCAUGAGCUACAGCGCUCAGCCGAAAGAUUAAUUUUUUAAAAAUGCCUCCUGUGACCUCCAUUUCUCUUCUACUUAGAGUCAGAGAGUGUUAAAACUUACAGACCAACUUAAUCCAAGCCCUCCAUUGGGCAGAUUGGGAUGCUGAGGAGAAGAUGGAGGGGGAUUUGUUUUUGGUAGCCUAGGGGUCCCACAGGAGAAAAGAAAGGAGGCAGUAGGACAGGAAAGGAAAAAUUUGGAGGCAGGUUUGGAGGGUAAGGGGUGAAAUAGCUGGCUUGGGCUACCAGAGGAUCUGGAGCAGGCACCCUUGGCCUUUAUAGUUGCAGGGACCCAUUUGGCAGGCUGGUGAAGUCUAUGAAUCCCUUCUCAGGAAGUGUUUUAAAUGCAUGAAAUAAAAUGAAAGACAUUGGAUUCUAAAGAAAACCAAAUAUAUUGAAAUAUAGUUACCAAAAUAUUUUAAAAACAAAUGUGUGAUUUAGUAAUACAAGUACUUCUUUAUUAAUGCAUUAAAUAACAAGAUCUAGUGAUGAGUCUAAUAAUUACCAUAAUUUUAAAGUAGUUAUGAGCAUAAGUGAGCUAUGAGAACAUGUGGGAUUUCUCAGCCUGGCAUGGUAGCUCAUGCCUGUAAUCCCAGCACUUUGGGAGGCUGAGGCGGGUGGAUCACCUGAGGUCAGGAGUUUGAGACCAGCCUGGCCAACAUGGUGAAACCCUGUCUCCACUAAAAAUACAAAAAUUAGCCUGGCAUGGUGGCAUGUGCCUGUAAUCCCAGCUCCUUGGGAGGCUGAGACAGAAGAAUUGCUUGAACCUGGGAGGCAGAGGUUGCUGUGAGCCAAGAUCGCACCAUUGCACUCCAGUCUGGGCGACAAGAGCAAAAUUCCAUCAAAAGAAAGAGAGAGAGAGAGAGAAGAAAGAAAGAAAGAAGGAAAGAAAGAAAGAAAGAAAGAAAGAAAGAAAGAAAGAAAGAAAGAAAGAAAGAAAGAAAGAAAGAUUUCUAAAUGCUAGAUUUCAGUUAGAUGCUAUUACAAAUAACAAUAUAAUUUAGGCCAGGUAUGGUGGUUUACAACUGUAAUCCUAGCACUUUGGGAAGCCAAGGCAGGAAGAUCACUUGAGCCCAGAAGUUUGAGGCUGCAGUCAGCUAUGGCUCUGUCACUGAACUCCAGCCUGGGCAGAGAAAGACCAUGUCUCUAAACAUAUAUAUAAUUUAUUUUCCAUCCAUAUUCUCAAACUCCUGGCUAAGAGCCCUGAUCAAGAGAGAUGGCACAGUGGCUGGACAUAGUGGCUCACACCUGUAAUCCCAGCACCUUGGGAGGCUGAGAUGUGCAGAUCACUUGAGGUCAGGAGUUGGAGAACAGCCUGGCUAACACGGUGAAACCCCAUCUCUACUAAAAAUACAAAAAUUAGCUGGGGGCCUGGUGCAGUGGUUCACGCCUGUAAUCUCAGCACUUUGGGAGGCAGAGGCAGGUGGAUCACCUGAGGUCAGGAAUUUGAGACCAGCCUGGCCAACAUGGUGAAACCCUGUCUCUACUAAAAAUACAAAAUUAGCCAGGCGUGGUGGUGUGUGCCUGUAAUUCCAGCUACUUGGGAGGCUGAGGCAGGAGAAUCGCUUGAACCUGGGAGGCAGAUCUUGCAGUAAGCCGAGGUCGCGCCACUGCACUCCAGCCUAUCGACAAGAUCGCAACUCCGUCUCAACAGAAACAAAAAAAGAAGAAGAAGAACAAGAAGCCGUGUGCAGUGGUGCAAACCUGUAAUCCCAGCUACUUGGGAAGCUUAAGCAGGAGAAUCACUUUGAAGCCGGGAGAUGGAGGUUGCGGUGAGCCAAGAUUGCGCUACUGCACUCCAGCCUGGGCAACAGAGUAAGACUCUGUCUCAAAAAAAACACAAAAAACAAACAACAACAACAACAAAAAACCACACACACCAAAAACAAAGAUGCCACAGGGGCUGCUUUAUUUCUUGAGGGCAUCAAGGAGGCCCCCAAGGAGAUGCCAGAGUGGCAGAGAGGCAGCCAGUGUUUGAGGAGGAAGGAGCAAGAGCAGGCAUCAUUCUGAAAGGCUACAAGCGUCCUCUGACACUCGAGGAUGUCUGGGAAGUUGAUGAAGAGAUGAAAACCAAGACAUUAGUGAGCAAGUUUGAAACGCACAUGAAGAGAGAGCUGCAGAAAGCCAGGCGGGCACUCCAGAGACGGCAGGAGAAGAGCUCCCAGCAGAACUCUGGAGCCAGGCUGCCUGGCUUGAACAAGAAUCAGAGUCAAAGCCAAGAUGCCCUUGUCCUGGAAGAUGUUGAAAAGAAAAAAAAGAAGUCUGGGACCAAAAAAGAUGUUCCAAAAUCCUGGUUGAUGAAGGCUCUGUUCAAAACUUUCUACAUGGUGCUCCUGAAAUCAUUCCUACUGAAGCUAGUGAAUGACAUCUUCACGUUUGUGAGUCCUCAGCUGCUGAAAUUGCUGAUCUCCUUUGCAAGUGACCGUGACACAUAUUUGUGGAUUGGAUAUCUCUGUGCAAUCCUCUUAUUCACUGCGGCUCUCAUUCAGUCUUUCUGCCUUCAGUGUUAUUUCCAACUGUGCUUCAAGCUGGGUGUAAAAGUACGGACAGCUAUCAUGGCUUCUGUAUAUAAGAAGGCAUUGACCCUAUCCAACUUGGCCAGGAAGGAGUACACCGUUGGAGAAACAGUGAACCUGAUGUCUGUGGAUGCCCAGAAGCUCAUGGAUGUGACCAACUUCAUGCACAUGCUGUGGUCAAGUGUUCUACAGAUUGUCUUAUCUAUCUUCUUCCUAUGGAGAGAGUUGGGACCCUCAGUCUUAGCAGGUGUUGGGGUGAUGGUGCUUGUAAUCCCAAUUAAUGCGAUACUGUCCACCAAGAGUAAGACCAUUCAGGUCAAAAAUAUGAAGAAUAAAGACAAACGUUUAAAGAUCAUGAAUGAGAUUCUUAGUGGAAUCAAGAUCCUGAAAUAUUUUGCCUGGGAACCUUCAUUCAGAGACCAAGUACAAAACCUCCGGAAGAAAGAGCUCAAGAACCUGCUGGCCUUUAGUCAACUACAGUGUGUAGUAAUAUUCGUCUUCCAGUUAACUCCAGUCCUGGUAUCUGUGGUCACAUUUUCUGUUUAUGUCCUGGUGGAUAGCAACAAUAUUUUGGAUGCACAAAAGGCCUUCACCUCCAUUACCCUCUUCAAUAUCCUGCGCUUUCCCCUGAGCAUGCUUCCCAUGAUGAUCUCCUCCAUGCUCCAGGCCAGUGUUUCCACAGAGCGGCUAGAGAAGUACUUGGGAGGGGAUGACUUGGACACAUCUGCCAUUCGACAUGACUGCAAUUUUGACAAAGCCAUGCAGUUUUCUGAGGCCUCCUUUACCUGGGAACAUGAUUCGGAAGCCACAGUCCGAGAUGUGAACCUGGACAUUAUGGCAGGCCAACUUGUGGCUGUGAUAGGCCCUGUCGGCUCUGGGAAAUCCUCCUUGAUAUCAGCCAUGCUGGGAGAAAUGGAAAAUGUCCACGGGCACAUCACCAUCAAGGGCACCACUGCCUAUGUCCCACAGCAGUCCUGGAUUCAGAAUGGCACCAUAAAGGACAACAUCCUUUUUGGAACAGAGUUUAAUGAAAAGAGGUACCAGCAAGUACUGGAGGCCUGUGCUCUCCUCCCAGACUUGGAAAUGCUGCCUGGAGGAGAUUUGGCUGAGAUUGGAGAGAAGGGUAUAAAUCUUAGUGGGGGUCAGAAGCAGCGGAUCAGCCUGGCCAGAGCUACCUACCAAAAUUUAGACAUCUAUCUUCUAGAUGACCCCCUGUCUGCAGUGGAUGCUCAUGUAGGAAAACAUAUUUUUAAUAAGGUCUUGGGCCCCAAUGGCCUGUUGAAAGGCAAGACUCGACUCUUGGUUACACAUAGCAUGCACUUUCUUCCUCAAGUGGAUGAGAUUGUAGUUCUGGGGAAUGGAACAAUUGUAGAGAAAGGAUCCUACAGUGCUCUCCUGGCCAAAAAAGGAGAGUUUGCUAAGAAUCUGAAGACAUUUCUAAGACAUACAGGCCCUGAAGAGGAAGCCACAGUCCAUGAUGGCAGUGAAGAAGAAGACGAUGACUAUGGGCUGAUAUCCAGUGUGGAAGAGAUCCCCGAAGAUGCAGCCUCCAUAACCAUGAGAAGAGAGAACAGCUUUCGUCGAACACUUAGCCGCAGUUCUAGGUCCAAUGGCAGGCAUCUGAAGUCCCUGAGAAACUCCUUGAAAACUCGGAAUGUGAAUAGCCUGAAGGAAGACGAAGAACUAGUGAAAGGACAAAAACUAAUUAAGAAGGAAUUCAUAGAAACUGGAAAGGUGAAGUUCUCCAUCUACCUGGAGUACCUACAAGCAAUAGGAUUGUUUUCGAUAUUCUUCAUCAUCCUUGCGUUUGUGAUGAAUUCUGUGGCUUUUAUUGGAUCCAACCUCUGGCUCAGUGCUUGGACCAGUGACUCUAAAAUCUUCAAUAGCACCGACUAUCCAGCAUCUCAGAGGGACAUGAGAGUUGGAGUCUACGGAGCUCUGGGAUUAGCCCAAGGUAUAUUUGUGUUCAUAGCACAUUUCUGGAGUGCCUUUGGUUUCGUCCAUGCAUCAAAUAUCUUGCACAAGCAACUGCUGAACAAUAUCCUUCGAGCACCUAUGAGAUUUUUUGACACAACACCCACAGGCCGGAUUGUGAACAGGUUUGCCGGCGAUAUUUCCACAGUGGAUGACACCCUGCCUCAGUCCUUGCGCAGCUGGAUUACAUGCUUCCUGGGGAUAAUCAGCACCCUUGUCAUGAUCUGCAUGGCCACUCCUGUCUUCACCAUCAUCGUCAUUCCUCUUGGCAUUAUUUAUGUAUCUGUUCAGAUGUUUUAUGUGUCUACCUCCCGCCAGCUGAGGCGUCUGGACUCUGUCACCAGGUCCCCAAUCUACUCUCACUUCAGCGAGACCGUAUCAGGUUUGCCAGUUAUCCGUGCCUUUGAGCACCAGCAGCGAUUUCUGAAACACAAUGAGGUGAGGAUUGACACCAACCAGAAAUGUGUCUUUUCCUGGAUCACCUCCAACAGGUGGCUUGCAAUUCGCCUGGAGCUGGUUGGGAACCUGACUGUCUUCUUUUCAGCCUUGAUGAUGGUUAUUUAUAGAGAUACCCUAAGUGGGGACACUGUUGGCUUUGUUCUGUCCAAUGCACUCAAUAUCACACAAACCCUGAACUGGCUGGUGAGGAUGACAUCAGAAAUAGAGACCAACAUUGUGGCUGUUGAGCGAAUAACUGAGUACACAAAAGUGGAAAAUGAGGCACCCUGGGUGACUGAUAAGAGGCCUCCGCCAGAUUGGCCCAGCAAAGGCAAGAUCCAGUUUAACAACUACCAAGUGCGGUACCGACCUGAGCUGGAUCUGGUCCUCAGAGGGAUCACUUGUGACAUCGGUAGCAUGGAGAAGAUUGGUGUGGUGGGCAGGACAGGAGCUGGAAAGUCAUCCCUCACAAACUGCCUCUUCAGAAUCUUAGAGGCUGCCGGUGGUCAGAUUAUCAUUGAUGGAGUAGAUAUUGCUUCCAUUGGGCUCCACGACCUCCGAGAGAAGCUGACCAUCAUCCCCCAGGACCCCAUCCUGUUCUCUGGAAGCCUGAGGAUGAAUCUCGACCCUUUCAACAACUACUCAGAUGAGGAGAUUUGGAAGGCCUUGGAGCUGGCUCACCUCAAGUCUUUUGUGGCCAGCCUGCAACUUGGGUUAUCCCACGAAGUGACAGAGGCUGGUGGCAACCUGAGCAUAGGCCAGAGGCAGCUGCUGUGCCUGGGCAGGGCUCUGCUUCGGAAAUCCAAGAUCCUGGUCCUGGAUGAGGCCACUGCUGCGGUGGAUCUAGAGACAGACAACCUCAUUCAGACGACCAUCCAAAACGAGUUCGCCCACUGCACAGUGAUCACCAUCGCCCACAGGCUGCACACCAUCAUGGACAGUGACAAGGUAAUGGUCCUAGACAACGGGAAGAUUAUAGAGUGCGGCAGCCCUGAAGAACUGCUACAAAUCCCUGGACCCUUUUACUUUAUGGCUAAGGAAGCUGGCAUUGAGAAUGUGAACAGCACAAAAUUCUAGCAGAAGGCCCCAUGGGUUAGAAAAGGACUAUAAGAAUAAUUUCUUAUUUAAUUUUAUUUUUUAUAAAAUACAGAAUACAUACAAAAGUGUGUAUAAAAUGUACGUUUUAAAAAAGGAUAAGUGAACACCCAUGAACCUACUACCCAGGUUAAGAAAAUAAAUGUCACCAGGUACUUGAGAAACCCCUCGAUUGUCUACCUCGAUCGUACUUCCUUGCUACCCACCCCUCCCAGGGACAACCACUGUCCUGAAUUUCACGAUAAUUAUUCCUUUGCCUUUCAUUUCUGUUUUAUCACCUUUGUAUGUAUCUUUAAACAACAUAUACCCUUUUUUACUUAUGUAAAUGGACUGACUCAUACUGCAUACAUCUUCUAUGACUUGAUUCUUUUGUUCAAUAUUAUAUCUGAGAUUCAUCCAUGGUGAUGCAAAUAGGUGCAUUAUUUUUUUUCACUGCUCUGUAGUCUGGCAUUGUAUGAAUACAGCACAAUGUAUCAGUUUUAAUAUUGGGGAUCAUUAGCAUUAUUCUCAGGUUUUUAAAAAUUAUAAGCAGUACUACUAUGGACAUUCUGGUCUACAUCUCCUGGCACAUAUGUAAGAGUUUCUCUAGGGUAUAACCUAGGAAUGGAGGGUAUGAACAUGUUUACAUGCACAAACUAGCUGAUGCCAAACUGGUAAUGCCAACUGAAAACAUUGCUGUCAAUCUGAUGAAUAUGAAUUGAUGUAUCAAUGAGAAUUUCAUUUGCAUUUCCCUAGUAUCUAUUGGGGAUGAAUAUAUUUUCAUGUUUCUGGGGCAUUUGCAUUUCCACUUGUUUUUUAAAUAUUGUGUCUGAUAAUUCCAAUGUCUGGAUUCUUUGUUUAUCUGUUGUUUCUGUUGGUUUUUACUCAUGGUAUUUUAUUUCCUUGUAUGUCUUGUGAAUUUUUAUUAUAAGCUCGUUCUCCUUAAAACUUUAUCUGUGGACAUUC